CGCCGGGCACCUUCAAGGUUUUGUUAAUUUUGGAUAAUGCUACAAUCCAUUGCUGCAAAGAACUCGAAAAUGCACACGCCAACAUAGGAGUUCUUUUUAUGCCCCCAAACACUAAGUCUCUCAUCCAACCCCUCAAUCGGGGCAUAAUAAAAGCAUUCAAGGCACACUACACAAGGGAGCUUUAUAUGAAGGCCUGUGAGGCUCUCAGGACCAACAAGGAAACCACCAUGCUGGACUAUUGGAAGUCGGUCACUACAUGCAACGUUAUUGAUUAUGUCAGUACAGCCUGGGAGAGCAUUGGUCAGGCUACUACCAAUAACUGUUGGGAAAAUGUUUGGCCAGACUGCGUGGAGAAUUUUGAAGGGUUUGAAGGUGUUACAGAAAAUAUAAAGAACACUGUCAGAGACAUAAUGCAUAUGGCACAGCAGGUAAGUGGAGAGGGCUUUGAUGACGUGAAGGAAGGAGAUGUGGAGUACAUUUUGGCAGAGAAGGCAGUGGAACCAACCAACGAAGACCUGGAUGAGAUGGCAAAAGAAGGCAUUGGAGUUGAUGGCCAUGAAAGUCGGCCCAAGACUUCCAGAAUUGUCCCUCUCACAGCGCCAAAAUAUCAGAAUGGAGUUCUGCCUUGGAAAAAAUUUUUAGCGACAUGGAAGAGUGUGACCCUACGCUUGAUCGAAGCCUCAAAUUUAAAUGGCUGGCCUCCACUGCGUUUGCCCCUUAUACCGAGAUGCUUAAAGAUUUCAGGCAGAAAAGCCAGGCAGGCAAGGCUAAUGCAAUUUCUCAAGCCAGUUUGGGAGGGAAGAUUGCCCACUCCUUCAACAAGUGUCAAGAGCCAGACUCCUAAGGUAGAAAUGCCAGAGGUUGACCUGCCACCCUCUUCCUCUUCUGCAGAAUAAAUUUCACUCACCCCUCCCCUGGUUUCUGUGGGGCAAGCCAAGGUCGAGAGGUUUAACCACAUUGUGCAGCUCCAUCAACCGUAAGAUUUUAGUUGAUAUUUUUAUAAAACUUAGGAUGCUC